AUAUAGUGUUUUUUUUCAUUUUCCAGACAUGUAGAACUUUAUUUUGCUAUAUUGUGUUAUGGGUUGCAACUUUAUUGCACUCUGAUCAGAAAACAUAUUCCAUAUAAUAGCUAUUGUGUAGAAUUUUUUAAGAUAUUUUAUAUUAAUAGCUUGAUACAUAAACAGUUUUUAUUUAAUAAUCCUCAUUUAUGCAAAAAGCACCCUUGUUCCAUAUUUAGAUGUGAAGUUUAUGUGUGUGUAUGUGUAUAUAUAUAUAUAUUUUUUUUUUUUUAUGGUUUUUUGUUUUUUUUUUGAGAUGGAGUCUCACUCUGUCUCCCAGGCUGGAGAGCAGUGGUGCCGUCUCAGUUCACUGCAACCUCUGCCUCCUGGGUUCAAGUGAUUCUCCUACUUCGGCCUCCCAAGUAGCUGGGAUUACAAGUAUGCGCCACCACACCCAGCUAAUUUUUGUAUUUUUAGUAGAGACGUGGUUUCGCCAUGUUGGCCAGGCUGUUCUCAAACUCCUGACCUCAGGUGAUCUGCCCACCUUGGCCUGCCAAAGUGCUAGGAUUACAGGCAUGAGCCACCAUGCCCAGCCAUAUUUUUUUAUAUAUAAAUAAGAUUAAUAAUACAAACACAUAUACACAUUUUUUCUGUACUAUGGCUUAUAUUUUGUCUAUUUGAUCUACCAAAUCUGAAAAAGCAUAUAUUAAAAUCACCAGUUACCAUCAUUUAUUUCUUCCUGUAAUCCUACCAGUGGUAGUUUUAGAUAUUUUACAUCUUUGUUGUUAACUGCAUAUAUGUUGAGGAUUAUUACAACUUCUUUAUUUAUAAUAUCUCUCUUGUCCUUUAUGGUGCACUUUGUCCCAAAUUAUAUUUUGUCUCAUAAUAAAAAAUUAACUCUGGCUUUCUUUUGCUUUAUAUUUGUUUCACAGCAUCUAUUUUUUCCAUCUUAUGUAUGUAUUUUUUCCAACUUAUGUAUGCCACCUUAUUUCAUAUUUUACAAUGUCCAUUCUUUUUUCUUAUUUCUUUUUUAAGUCUUUCUACCUACUUGCCAUUAGGUACAUCAAAUUUUCAUCUGCUGCUUUAAAGUUAUACAUUUGUAUUUUAUUACCUUGACUUAUUUUGACUUAGUCUUAGGUUAUUUUUUCCUGGCAAUAUAUAAAGCAGAUCAAUAUCUAUGUCUUUAUCGUUUAACAAAAUAAUACCCAUAGCAUACCAUCCUCUACCUCUCCUCUUGUUGCCAACUUUUUGUAUUUCAGGAGUUUUAGUUACAUAUAUUUGUAAGUGUACUUUUUACAAAAUAAUUAGUUCCAGCUCACCUAUACUUCUUUCUGUCCAACUGUAAUGGGAUUCUGGUGCUGCCCUAGUGUUAAUUCACUAUUAUCUCUGGUGCUGCAGCUUACCUACCACAUUACACCAAAGGUUUCUACCAAAGGCACCAAAGGAUAAUAAGUUAGUGUCUAGGAGGUCUAAGCUUCAGGGCCUGAAAUAGGCUAUCCCUGAUGUACCUCCAGAUACAGGCUUACUCAGGUUAUGUGGAGAAGACUAAAGAUUAAAUUGCUGGCCCCCAUUCCUGGUUACUGUACUCUCCUGCUUCAGAUCCUCAGUUUUCCAAAGACAUCUGCAACUACUUGUGUUCUGUAUGAGUUUCUCAUCAGCUGUUUUAUUAAUUGAUGAAUAAGACCCUGAAGCCCAUACAAAGUCUAUUUUUCUUUUUUGGCAUCUCCGAAGUUGAAUUCAAGAGAGACAGGGAAUAGCUCAUGUUAGUUUGCUAUGUUGUACUGCACUGGCACUUUCCCCCUCCCUAACUUUGUAUUUUUAUUUAUUCCAUCAUCCUGUUUCUCUUAGGAAUGUUUGAUUACUCAUAUUCUAACUUCUUGAAACCAAUGCUGAAUUUAUUGUCAUACUUGAUUGUUUAAAUAUGAGAGCAGUUAAAAUUAUGAACCUGUCUCUUAUUAUGCCUUUGGCCACAUCUCGUUUCAACGUGCAUUCUUCUCAUUUUCAUCACUUCAUAAAUAGUCUAUAUUUUUUAUUUUUACUUUCAUUUUCUCUUUGACUUGAACAAUUGGGGAAACUUUUUAAUUUGUAACUUUUUAAUCUAUUUAAUGUUUUAUUACAUUGAGGCCAGAUAAUAGUGUCUUUUCAAGUUUUUCUUUUUUUGAAUGUGUUGCUUUUAUUGUAGACUAAUACUGGUGUUUUUGGUAAAAGUGACACGAUGUGUUUUAGACCUUCUGGAUCCAUAUUCAUUUUUCCUUAAUCUAGGAAAUUGAGAAUUAUAUAUACUGAAAUUAUACCUCAUUGUUGUAUUUUGUGUCUUACAGCUUUGGUUAUCUAUGUUGAUGGCAUGUUGAAAGUACAUAAAAUAUGACUUCAAGAUUUAUCAACCUUUAAGUAUACUUUGAUGUUAAUAUUCUUACUGCUACUUUUGUUUGCAGUUGCUGGAUAAACACCAGUGUAUAAGUGUGUACCUAUUUUUAACAUAAACAUAAUUGUAGCACUUUGUUUUAUAGUAGCUUUAAAAUAAUAUAAUCACCUGUGGUUCCAGCUAUUCAGAGGGCUGAGGUGGGAGGAUCACGUUAGCCUGGGAGGUAGAGGCUUCAGUUGAGUGGUGAUUGUGCCAUUGCACCCCAAUCUUUGCAAGAGAGUGAGACCUUGUCUCAAAAUAAAUAAACAAAUAAAAAUAUAAUAUUGGAAUCUGUAUUUUUUACAAGAAAAUUUAACCAAUUUAAGUUUAUAAUUAUAAUUAUGCAAGAUAUAGGUGUUCCCACCUUAUUUUAUGCUAUAUGUUUCUUUUAUGUUUAUUGGCUUUCACACUAAGGCUUGUCUUUAAGUUUUUGAAAAGUGUUUAAAAAUUUAAGGACAAAAUAAAAAUUAAAAUAUUAAAAAUGAAAUUAAAAUUUAAUUUAAAAAUUAAAAAUUAAGAACAAAAUAUAAUUUGAAUUCAAAUAAUCAUUUGAAUGUUUCAUAUGGAAGAUUUUGAUACACUCUUGGGUUCUAAGCGAGAUUAUUAAAAUAUAAUUGUUACAUUUUUUAAAAACUUAUGUUUUUGGUUAGUUUUCUAAAGAUAUUUACAACAGAUAGUUAUACUCUCAGGUUAAUCAGUAUCCACUAUUAUUCCUUUUAAAGAAUAAUUUCUUCAUUCUUAUAUUCUGAAUUUUUUCUCAUUCUCAGAGUAUAUCUUUAAGUAAUUUGUUAAGUAUUUGUGGAGGAUAUAGUUUCCAUGAGCUUCCCAUACUGAGAAUGACAUUCUAAUUCAUUUAUGAACUUUUUCCCUGAAAAAGUGGUAGGGCAAGUUUUAUUGUUUUAAGAGUGUUUUAAAGGAAAAGUCUAACAUAAAGCUUGCAUUUGGAUGCUUGUAUUGUUUUCACCUUGUACUUUAAAAAUCUUUAGCACAAUUUAUUGAAGUAGGCCUUCUUUCAUUGAUUAUUUGUCUUUUUAAUUUGCUUUCAUUGCUCUGUUUUUGUUUUGUUUUCAUUUUAGUUCAUUAAUGUUUCCUUCAGUUUUUUCCUAUUUCUGUUUUUUUUCUAGAAAUACUGUCAUCAGUAUCUAUUACGUUUUUUUAUGGUUUUAUUUUGUCUUUUUUUCGUGUCUGAGAUUGUUUCUUAAAUUUGUCUUGUCAUAUCAGUGAUUUUAUUUUUUAUAGCAUUAAUUAUGCUUUUUGUUAAUUUUUUAUUGGGUAAAAUAUACAUGUAUAGUUUACUGUCUUUACCAUUUUAAGUGUACAGUUUAAUUGUAAUUAAAUAUGCUUUUAAAUUCAAAUUCAUUUAUGCUUUUUAGCACUUCUAACAUGACUUAAUUCUCUUAUUAAAUGUUUAGUCUUCUUACUCUUCAUUCUUUCUCGCUUUUCUUUACUUUCUCUUCAGCCUAGAAUUUCAAAAAGUGAUCUUAAAAUAUUUUUUUACUUAUGGGAUACAUCAUUUUCACAAGUUUACUUAUUUGUGUGUUCAAGUUGAUAUUUUCUUUACCUUGAUUUGCAGUAUUUGUUAAUAGACCUAAGGUGACCUGUUUUUUCUUUCCUUAUCUUGAAAUGAAACAAAAAUCUUUUAGUAGGUUAGUCAGUAAUUAUUCACUUUUUGAUUAUGAAUCUCAUUUCUAGACUUAGAUCAGGAGGGAUAUUUAGGUGCCUCGUGUCCAGCCCAGUUGCUAUUUUCUAGCAGUCUGACAUCUAGGGCAAUUCUCUGUACUAAGGUCAGAUACUCCCAAGUAUUGCCACACAGUUCUCUAAGUUAAAGAGAUAAAAAAGGUAAUUUCCAGUCUUCACUGCUAGCAAGGCACUUACUGAAGCCACCCAUGUCUAUAUAGGUCUGCAGCUGAAAGUAUGCAGUGUGCCAUGCAUCAGCCACCUUCCUGCAUUUCCCCCUAACAGUUGCUUUCUGAGCAAAUAUGGAAUACUGAGGAAGUUAGAGAGCCCAGUUUGAGGCCCCAUUCCUGGGCAAGACAGUAGGGGUUGUCCACUUUUUGCUUGGGACAGAAUGGAUCUCAAGCCAUCAGUGAGGGUGGUACAAAGUGUCUCCCUGAUGUCAGAGGGGAUCUUGGAUAGAUUUUUCUUAAUUCAACUUCAUGACUCUUUUAUAUUCUAUGAACUGUUGUUUUUAGUUGUGGUGUUCAUUUUUGAUUGUGAGUUUUUUUGUUUUUAAUGUGAUUACACUGGCAGUUUAAUGGAAGGUACGGCGAGGCUGGCUCAGGAACUGUUAGCCAGGUACCAUUUAAAGUGACUGUCCAAUUUCUCCCUUGCCAUUCCUCCUCAGGAGUCACAGCAAUUGCAACAAUUAAAAAAAUUCGACAUUUCUCUUGAAGAAAAAAUGGAGUCUAAAAGUUGGUUUAUUUUAUUUAUUUAAUUCUAUGAAAAAGAAUCUAGAAAAGUUAUAAAAUGCAUGGGAUAAUAACAUUAAGUUAUCUUUAUGGAAGUUUCCACUACCAUGUAGGGAAGCUAUAAAUUGCUGCCUACUUAAUAGCAAACAGUUACUUAUUUAAAAAAGAGCUGUAAUUACAGGCCAUCAACUACAUCCAGCAGCAGCAUCAUUAAUAACAAGUUUAUGAGUACCUACUUAGGGAGUGACCUUGUUAGAGAAUCUCACCCAAUGCUACAUAUGCUGCCAUUAGUGUUACCAUUCAGAUUAGAUUGUGAUAUUGUUCAGUCAGCCAGUUUUAGUUCAUUUUGCAUACAUGAUUCCCUAAGUAAAACACUUUCGUUAAUACUGGAUAGAUACCAUAUGUAAACUUUUCAGCAGAAAUUACAAAGAAAUAUGGCAAAGCUUCAUCUUAACACCAAAAUGUAGUUAAAAACAGCUUUGAUUUCUUUUGUGAAGCUAUAUUGUUGUAGGUAAGACAUACAUCACUCAAAUACUCACAAAGAUAACUAAAAAUUUAGAUCCCAAUCUAGAAAGCACUUUAUAAAGUUCUAUGCAAAUAUUAGUUAUUGAUUUGCUUUUGUAAAGCAACAGCAGAAAAUGUUGCCCUUAUCUGAUUGUAAUAUUUCUAGAACUAGAGCUCUCUUAAAACAUUUCCUGCAAAGAUAUUUUUCACUUUUUAAAGAAAAAUGUUUCCAUGCUCUCACAGGAUAAGUAGAGAGAGGGCAAAAGUUCAGUCUCACUAUUUAAGUUUCUGUGUAAAGGAUGUUUCUAUUUCUAGCACAGUUAUAUUUGGAUUAUAUCGAUCCGGUAAUAUGAGUGCAUGUUCUGUAUUCAUCUUUUUGAAAAAAAAAUUAUACACAGCAGGUACACCUUCAGAAUGUUAAAUGAAAGCUCCUGUUCUCAUAGGAAUGUGUAUGUUUAUUUGUGCUGAAAUCCUGAGGUGCAUAUCUAUGGCUUUCAUAUUAAAGAUGACUGAAGAGAUGAAAAUGAUGGUCUUGUAAGUUAAAAGACUUUUACCUGCAGUCCUUAACCUUUUCUUUUUAUUUAUGCCCUCCUAAUCCCAACUCUUUUCUCCAAACCUAGCUUCUCUGAAGCCCAAAAACUCCAACAGGCAUCUCAGGCUCUAUUUCUAUUAACCAGCCCUGUUAACCUUCUAUCCCUGCAGUCAGCGUGCCUGACCAUUCUUGCAAACUCUUGGACCUGUACUUUGAAAAGGUUAUUGAUUCUUGACAUAAAUCUCUUAAACAUGUGGAAAGGGAACUGCUCUAGAAUAAGAAAACUCAACCUUUUACCAACUAUGCUUCAUUUGUCGAGGUCCUUCACCCCUGUGAAAAGCAAUUUUCUUUUCCUCAUGAAAUGGAGAUAACUUGGGUCCAUCUUGCUCACUUUGCUUGGAAAGUAGGGUCCACGUCUGGACAAACAGGCCAAAGACACAUGACAUCUGAUCUGGCUAUAGGAACAAAAGACUAAACAAGCCAUCCAGCAGCAGGUUGCCUCUGACCUUUCUCACAGGGUGAUCUGGAGAAUUCUUACAAGGUGUUUUUAUUAAUCUCCCUGAAGUAUCUUGAAAGUAGAUUCUAUGUCAUGUUCAUGUAUCCUCAGUGAUUAGCAUAGUACCUAGCACGUAGUCUCAGUCACUAAAGGCCAAUUGAUUAUUAAGGGAGGUGGAGGUCUGCUUUCUAAGCUUCAUUAAUAAUAACAGCAGCUGAUUGAGCACCAUUUUGCAUUCACUGUCAGAAUGCUCAGAGACUACCAGAAGUGAUCCAUGGUUUCCAGUUGGAGUAAUAACUUCUCAUCUGAGAGGUUAUGAUGAUGACAUAUGGCUUGGGGUUUGGGGGAAGAUUAAAUGAAAAAUAUAUCCCAAAGCAACUGGUUCAGUUAGAUACAUGGUUAAGGGAGGAACAGAGGUAGGAAGAGUCAAAUCUGGUUUUGUUUCCGCUCCAUCACCUGUUUCUAGUGGGAACUUGAAAAGGUGUGUGACUUCCCUGAGCCUCUUUCCUCAUCUGAACCAUGAGGUUCACAACACCUGCCCUGCCUCCCCCAGUCAUUUGCAAUGAUAAAGGGAGAUGAUUAAAAAUAAAGGGGCCUACAAAUGUAAGAAAUUUAGUAUUAGUGGAAAGAACCAUGGGCUGGGAUUUCUAAAACCUGGCUUUGGCACCUAAUAGCCUUCCAAGGUAAGCUCACUAGACACAGGUCCAUACUAUAUAAAACAAAAAGGGUUCAGUUAGUGUAUUUUGAUGCUUUUCUUGUCAAAAGUGAUGGAUUUGUAGAAAUUCUCUUAAUGUACAUACAGAAUUAAAAUAAUCGCAUAUUUUUAAUUUUAGGCCUCAUGUGUACUAAGAAAAUCUUGUCCAUUCUGAAUAAUGUGAAUUUACACAAUUCAUUCUGCUUUCCUAUAUGUAAAGAAUUUAGCUAUACUUAGUAACACUCCAAACUUUGCGCAGUUGUUCUCACCUCACUGCUAAUUAGUUCAGUUCCCUCCUGUUAUCCAUUUUUGGUGAGAUGGAAAGGGUAGAAUAGAUCAACAUGGGCUGUUUCACAGUUUUACCUGGGUUUGUCCCACAAUUUGUGGAUUAAUCUAGUGUAUUUAUUCACAAGAAGGAAAAUAUUGGCUCAGGACAAGAAUUUCUAAGCUCUGCAACCUUGACAACUACCUUCAGGUUCUUUGUUUCAUAAAUGUCACACCUGUUGUAUGUGAAAGGGCCCUUGGAGUUCCUCACAUCUAGCAUUUUUCAUAUGGGAAACUGAGGCCCAGAGAAGCAACUUAUAGAAGACACAGUGAUCUGAGAAAAGAAAGUCCAAAAUGCCAACAAGCUGCAUGCCACGUAUUUGGUUACCCUACGAGGAGUUAAUAAAAUCUGUCACUUGCCCAUAGUGCAGUGUUCACUGUGGAAUCUGCCCUUUUGAUUUCUUGUUUCUCUUUAAAUUGAAUCAGAGGUGUUCAUUUUACUUCAGGUGUGACAUUUUACAGCAGUUAGCACAUUUAACUGAGAGGUGAAGCUGGGGUAAUCAUAUUUGAGUUAUUCAGAUCAUUCUUUCUUGGUCCUAGCUGAGUUUAUUGAGGACAUACUAUAUGCUAGCCACUGUGCUAAGUGCUUUAUAUGGGUUUUAUCACUUAAUCAUCCAAUAAGGAAGGUUAUGACUUAUAAGGAACUGAAUUUUACAGGCAAGGAAAGUGAAAUGAAAGAGGUUAAGUAAUUUUCUAAUGCUCCAUAGAGUACAUGGUAGACCAGAGAUGAAUUCAAGCAGUCUAAGUUAACUACUCUUCAUGCUUGGCACAUGGUUGAAAGAACAAGAAGUAUAUCUUGUCAAUAGCGAUUGCAAAUCCUAUAAAAUCACCUAAGUGUAUGGAUUUUCUGGAUGCCUUAGCACAUAGCCAUGUAUGUUUGUGUGCAUAUACAUUAUUUGUUUUUGUAGAUUUAUAUAUAAAUAAUGUGUCUAAUGUCUAAGUACUUUUGCCCUUUUUUACGUUAUUAGUUUAUACUGGUGGGGGAGAUUAGCCCUAAUAUUUAUUAGAGGGAGAAAAAGUCAUUUUUACAGCAUCCUGCACAUAGCAACUCUUCAACGAAUGCCUAUUGAAUUCAUCCUUAUUUUCUAAGGAAAGUGGCAAUGGAUCAGAACGAGAAGAUCCAGGUUUUAGUUCUGGUUUUAAUGGUGAUUCACUGUGAGGAAAAGACCAGGUUGGCUGUCUUCUCCAAUCUUUAGUCUUCCCGUGUCUAAAAUGAGUUCAGAAGAGCCUACAGUUGGAGCGUCCACUGGGCAUUCAAGCCUAUCUGACUGGCUAGCCUGGUGUGUCAGGAUUCCAAAAGAUCCAUCCAGACUAGGACUUAGGAUGAGUAUAGACCUCAUCAGUGAAGGGGUAGGAAUUGCAGGGAUUUCUGAGCAGCACUGUUGUGUCUUUACACCUUCUUCCAAUCUAGUCAUUGAGAAAACUUGUGAUUAGGUUCCUUGCCAGGUGCACUAAUACUCUGAGCAUCUGCUAAAGGCAGGUAAGUAAGAAUUGUACCACUUGUGCUGUGGUAAGAAACUAAAAGAGCCAGAUUUUGUGUCUUAUAAAAAUAACAUUUCCACAUAGGGUCCUACUCUAGAAACUGUUCAAGCAUAGAAGCCCCUAGGAGCCGGUGAGGGUGCAAGGAGCAAUAGCCACACCAGCAAGAUGGCCAGAGUGACCAGGUCAGGAAGAAUUGGAGCUGCUGAUCAGAAUGUGCUUGCAACUCACAGGACCAUAGCGCCACCUUUCUUGCAGAUUUGGAAUAAAUCUUCACACGUCCAGUUGCAAAUCAAACAUGCAGUUACAGAAGCAGAGAUUCAAAAAUUGAAGACCAAGCUGCAGGCAGCAGAAAAUGAGAAAGUGAGGUGGGAACUAGAAAAAACCCAACUCCAACAAAACAUAGAAGAGAAUAAGGAAAGAAUGUUGAAGUUGGAAAGCUACUGGAUUGAGGCCCAAACAUUAUGCCACACAGUGAAUGAGCAUCUCAAAGAGACUCAAAGCCAGUAUCAGGCCUUGGAAAAGAAAUACAACAAGGCAAAGAAGUUGAUCAAGGAUUUUCAACAAAAAGAGCUUGAUUUCAUCAAAAGACAGGAAGCAGAAAGAAAGAAAAUAGAAGAUUUGGAAAAAGCUCAUCUUGUGGAAGUGCAAGGCCUCCAAGUGCGGAUUAGAGAUUUGGAAGCUGAGGUAUUCAGGCUACUGAAGCAAAAUGGGACUCAAGUUAACAAUAAUAACAACAUCUUUGAGAGAAGAACAUCUCUUGGUGAAGUCUCUAAAGGGGAUACCAUGGAGAACUUGGAUGGCAAGCAGACAUCUUGCCAAGAUGGCCUAAGUCAAGACUUGAAUGAAGCAGUCCCAGAGACAGAGCGCCUGGAUUCAAAAGCACUGAAAACUCGAGCCCAGCUCUCUGUGAAGAACAGACGCCAGAGACCCUCUAGGACAAGACUGUAUGAUAGUGUUAGUUCCACAGAUGGGGAGGACAGUCUAGAGAGAAAGCCAUCAAACAGUUUCUAUAACCACAUGCAUAUUACCAAAUUACUUCCACCUAAGGGUUUGAGAACGUCUUCUCCAGAAUCAGAUUCUGGUGUUCCACCCCUCACCCCGGUGGAUAGCAAUGUGCCCUUCUCGUCUGACCACAUAGCUGAAUUUCAAGAAGAACCACUGGACCCAGAAAUGGGGCCUCUCUCCUCUAUGUGGGGAGACACUUCACUGUUUUCUACUUCAAAGUCUGAUCAUGAUGUGGAAGAAUCUCCUUGCCAUCACCAAACCACCAACAAGAAAAUAUUACGAGAAAAAGAUGAUGCCAAAGAUCCCAAAUCACUAAGGGCAUCCAGUUCAUUGGCGGUGCAAGGAGGAAAAAUUAAGCGGAAGUUUGUGGAUCUGGGGGCGCCUUUGCGAAGGAAUUCCAGCAAGGGAAAGAAGUGGAAAGAAAAAGAAAAAGAAGCCAGUAGGUUUUCUGCAGGUAGCAGGAUCUUCAGAGGCAGACUGGAAAACUGGACACCCAAGCCAUGUUCAACAGCUCAGACCUCCACUCGUUCCCCUUGCAUGCCUUUCUCAUGGUUUAAUGACAGCCGGAAAGGAUCCUAUUCCUUCAGGAACCUGCCUGCGCCUACAAGUUCCCUUCAGCCUUCUCCUGAGACUCUAAUUUCAGAUAAAAAGGGGUCCAAGGUAGAAAACACAUGGAUUACAAAAGCAAACAAGAGAAACCCAAAUCCCUCCUCUUCUUCAAUCUUUGGAAGGCAUUCUCAACUUAUGUCUGUAGUCUGGAUCCAAGAAACCAAUAAUUUUACCUUCAAUGAUGACUUCAGUCCCAGCAGUACCAGUUCAGCAGACCUCAGCGGCUUAGGAGCAGAACCUAAAACACCAGGGCUCUCUCAGUCCUUAGCACUGUCAUCAGAUGAGAGCCUGGAUAUGAUAGAUGACGAGAUCCUUGAUGAUGGACAGUCUCCCAAACACAGUCAGUGUCAGAAUCGGGCCGUUCAGGAAUGGAGUGUGCAGCAGGUUUCUCACUGGUUAAUGAGCCUAAAUCUGGAGCAGUAUGUAUCUGAAUUCAGUGCCCAAAACAUCACUGGAGAACAGCUCCUGCAGUUGGAUGGAAAUAAACUUAAGGCUCUUGGAAUGACAGCAUCCCAGGACCGAGCAGUGGUCAAAAAGAAACUCAAGGAAAUGAAGAUGUCUCUAGAGAAGGCUCGGAAGGCCCAAGAGAAAAUGGAAAAACAAAGAGAAAAGCUAAGGAGAAAGGAGCAAGAGCAAAUGCAGAGGAAGUCCAAAAAGACAGAAAAGAUGACGUCAACUACAGCCGAGGGUGCUGGUGAGCAGUAACACAUACCCUCUUACAGAUGAUGGAGAUGCUCCAAGAGAAGUCCCCACCUCUUCCUGCCCUGCUCUCCUCCAGAGGAUGAAAAAGAAACUAAAUGAUAAGGGUAAUGCGGCUCUAGGCCGGCUGAGGAACUGUGUGUUGAAUAACUGCAUUUUCUGCAAUAGAAUGCACUCUUAAUUUUAACUACUAAAAUAAUCCCAAGCCACCUUUGGUUCAUUAACAAACCAGAGAUUUCAUUUAAGUAGCUGUGUUUUGCUCUUCUCUAACUUACCAACAUCUUGUGUUGUGUUGGGUGUGUUUUGUCACUUGGAGAACUAGUGUGACCCCACCCAAGAGCAUGACACACCCUGGUGUUGUUAAUGGAGCGCCGUGAAUUUUCAGUGUGGGAUCCUGAAAUGGCAAUUGCACAUGUCUGCAUGGCAGAGAGCACCCUGCCAUGAGAUCUGAGACCAGUACUUAACUUCUAGGACUGCAACACCUACUCCAAUGUGUGGGAAAGAUUUGCUCUUAAUUCUCAGUCUGGACAGUGAGACCACCCCGCUGUGGAAACAUGGGUGCUCUGCUCUGUAGUUACCUACUAAGGGAAAAGGCAAGCAAGUCAUUCUGCUUGCUAGGCAUCAAAAAGAAAGAAAAUAAAUUAUAGCUAUUUGUUAACCACUGAAAAAAGCAAAAGCCUUAAGAAUGUGGAUGUGGGUAUUACCUUGGGGUUCUGAGGGUAAUAUUUAUCCUCUAGAUACGGCUGAACAAGAAAGAAAAAAAUCAGACAUUAAUGCAGCCAUGGGAUAUUGGGAUCUGUUGACCUUGCUACUGCUGUGUGUUCAGCAUUUCAGCAACACUGGCAAACACAACACAGUUCCUCUUCCCCCUACCUAACCCAAGAAAUUGAACAGGAAAUUGAUUUUUAAGGAAACCACCAUUUUCAGGUUUCCUCUCCUGGGGAACAUUCUGGCUGGUCUUCAGCCUGCCUAUGUCACAAUCAGGAACUCAUCACAUAUUUUCUACUCAAGAUUUCCCAGGUGGGCUCAGUUAGUAUUUUAACAAAUGUACUUUUAAGAAAAAUAGAAAUACCAGUUAGAGGAAACUGUCAGUUAACAUUUUAGAGAGAUUUUGAAUGGUUUUUCCGAACCAUUCCUUUCCAUACUUCAAAGAUUCUCAAUUUUACAGAAAAAGUUUGUUUAAGGCAGUGCAUAGGUAUACUUUAGUAGUGGAGGAACUUAUACUAAUUUUAAGCCAGCAUUAAGGAUUUCCAUGUUUCACCAAACUAAGUCAAGUGCAGGAGACUGGGGCAGAAGAAGGAGAAAAUAAACUCGUUUUGAGAAAUUUCAUGUGAUGAGGGUUUUUUGUUUUUUAUGCUCAUGUAUCUGGUUCUCUUUGCUGCGUUGACUCUAAAAAUGAGGUUAUCCACUUUCCAAAGGACAAGUUUCAGAAUAAGACUUGAGGCCACAUGAAUUCUUGGACAGUAUUUUACUUCUUUUACUUUAUGGGAAUCUCUGCUCUGUUCCCAGCAUCUCGUAUCUUCCACUAGAAGUAUUCCAUAUUUAGAGCCUCGGCAAGGCUUUUGAGUGUAACAGAUUAAGGGAACUCCCUUGUAGCCCCAUCUUGUAUUUUAAUAACAGUGUGAUUUUUUUUUAUCUGAAAAUCUGAAUUCAGAAAUUAUCUAAACUGGACAUUUUUAAUUCUGUUUUACCCCCAAGGCCUGUUUUCUUUUCAUUGCCAGAGUAUUGUCGGUUAUGCGUCAGCUCUUUUGUCAUUAGGUACAGACCCUUCAUUCAAUCCUCAGAAACGUUGACAUGAAGUAACAUUGUGUUUUACAGUUAUCAAAGUCACCAUUAUGUUUUUCUGUCUGUCUUCAUUAGGGGUAUGAUAAUGAAACUGCCGUAUUGGAUACUCUAUUAAUGUCUUGAGAUGUCUGGUGCUUUGUUAUUUUUUCACAUCAUGAGAAAUAAGAAGCCACUAUUAAUGAGUGAUACAAUUUGGCAAAACUUUUCAAAUACUAAAACACUAAAUUAGUAAAAAUCUGGUAAUAUUAGUGCUUGCUAUUGUAAAUUUUUGCCAUUUUUGCUUAUCUUUGGGAAAAAAGUGACCUGGAUCACACUGGAAGUUUCACUGUAUUCAAGAGUAGAAAUAGAAGGAUGAUUAUCUUAAGUUAUGUUUACACUUUGGUAAUAUUUGAAAAUGGAUGUAUAUACUGGAAAUGUCUGUAAGUGUCUUGUUUUUGCACCUAAUUUAUGAUCUAUUAUAUUGCAUUUUCUUAAAUAUCUUAGAAGUAUUUUUCUUUAUAACUUUGUAUAUUGAAUGUUUAGAUAAAUGUCCAACUGACAAUGUUAUAAAUCAAAUUCUUAUUCCUAAAAUCAUUUAGUAUUAUAAGUAUUUUGAUUUUUUAAGUUAAAUUAUAGUAAUUUUAGGCCGAAGUGAGUUAUUUUAACAUUACCACUUAAAACGGAUGAAAUUGUAAAAGUCAUUUGGUUUGAUUGCCCCACAAAGCAUAAGAUGUAAACUGAUUAAGGGUAUGAAAGCAAAGUGAAAGACCUCAGAUCUUGUGCACAUUUUGUUUUCCUAUUAUUUCUUUUAUUGACUGUAGUGCAUGAUACCUAAUCAAGGCUCCAAUGUCUUGCACAAUUCCUACUUUAAUGCUAGUGGUUUUCAGUGUCCUUACAAUUUAACACAGAAUUGUUAUUUCAUCAACCUUAAAAACUGCAGUUUUUAUUAUCAGAAAAUGAACAAAAAGGGAAUAUCUGGUUGCUAUGAACUGAUUCCCUAAAGGAGAGCUCAGUAUGAUUCUAACAAUAGCCAAAAGUGUUUUGGGGUAUAGGUUAUGCUUUGUUGGGAGGGAAUGUGUGGUGAGGAGGCCAAGCUGCAGACAGAAAGCAUUGUAUGAGCUGUAUCUGGGUCAGGGUUUCCCAUUAAAGGAUGUUAGUUUUAUAACAGAUUACUUUGUUUAAGACCAUCUCCCUUCAAGUAACUCACAGUUUAUGUAAUACUAAUCUCAUUCUUUUUUUACCUGAAUCAGGAAUUUUCUGCAGAAUGUUAAGUUAGGGAAGAAACCUCAUUUCAUCCAUUCUAACACUCCUGAUGAAGUCCCCCUUUAGUUUCAUGACAAUAAAGCUGUUCUGUGGCUAUCAUCCUUUAGCUGGGAUUGACAAUUGAUUUCACACCCUCAACAUCACAAGCUUUUUUUAACCCACAGCAGUUCAUGAUUGCAGUAUGAUAGGUACUAAAGCCAAACUCAGCUUUCAACUGGCACAAAAUGGGACUGUCACCUUUUGCUCCAUUGUUGUUGGAAACAAAGUGGCAAGAGGGAAAAUGAGGAACCAGAUUUACCUUUGCCACUAUCUGUGACCCUGUAAUCAUCACUAGCCUGAAAUCUUAAAAUAUCCCAGUCCCAAGCUACAAAAAUGGUCACAGGUGGUUUGAUCUAGCACCUCGGCCGUUAGAGUUUGUGCUGAAGACAAAUUUGUCUGGGUUCAUUGUGCACCAGAAUUAGCAUGUGCUUGAAAAUUGCAUUUUAUAAAAGGGAAAUGAAAAUUUGCAUUUAUAUAGAUACUCUGAUUCAUGUUUAAGUGUUAAAGGUUAUGCAGACUAAACUUCAAGAGGAGAUCCAGUGUUUAACAAUAGUGUUCUAGAGGAUUCUAAAGGAAGCUGCCCCAGCAGCCCUGAGAGAACCAUCUAUACUUUGGAUAUGUUGUAGCCCCAUCAUUACACUGAGAUAUUUCCAUUUGAGUAACUAAAGGUACUCCUGACAGAGCUGGAGAUGAGGGGCAUUUUGGUGGGCAGUGGUCACUAGGGUUCACGUCACCUACUUAAUGCAAAGACCUUAGUGGUCUCAGAAUGAAAAGGUAAAAUGGAAGAGAAAAGCACAGUCCUUUCCUGUCUUUUCAAAUUUACUUUUUAUUAAGGAUGUACCUGUGCACUAUUCUAAAGCUAAGCAUUUAAGGAUAAAGUCCAGAAAUAAAAUGUCCAUAUUUUCUUUUCUUUUCUUUUUUUUUUUUUUUUUCUGUCAUCUGUCACCCAGACUGGACUGCAGUGGUGCCAUCAUGUCUUACUGCAGCCUCAAACUCCUGGGCUCAAGUGGUCCUCCUGCUUCAGCUUCCCAAGUAGCUGGGACUACAGGCAUGUGCCACCACCCCCAGCCAAAACAUCCAUAUUUUCUAUUAGAAUGGUUUACAUUAUGAUGGGGGAUGGGGAGCUGGGGGAGGGCUGUACAUUCCCAAAAGAAAGUAGUGUUAUAGGAAAUCCAAAUGCGCUUCAGUGAUUCACUCCUGAAAAGCAGCCUGGGUAUGUUGGCAGAUUUUGUUUGCAUUUGUCUUGCGUAUUUAAAGUCUCAGGAAAUCUAGUCUUGGUCCAAAACACUGGAGAAAAAAAUAACACCAGACAAAACACAUUUGAGUAACUUGAAGUAGCAGCAUAGAAUAGGCCCAACUAAGAAGUUGGAGGGGCAAAGAGAAAGCCGACAGAAUCAGCUUCUCCUGGAAAGUGAAAGCAUCAAGUUCUAUUUAUGGUAGACAGAGGGUCCUUAUUUGCUUGUCCGUGGUGUCUAUGUGGGCCUAUUGAGGGAAUGGUAGUUACUUGAAGGUUCACAUAUGUAAGCGUGUGGACCCAGCACAGUCUGUGACCUGAUUCCAGAUCCUCAAGAGUGGAGAAGGAAAGAAAUAUGAUGAUUUCCUAUGCUUGACCCUAACCCAACCCCAAAACUGCUAGGGAUUCAACAGUGAGUAAGAUGUAUGCAAUAAGAGAACAGAUAACUUCUCAACAAUGUGCAUGCCGUUUGUGUAGAUGUUCAGAACUACAUAUGUGUGAAUAUCACUCCCACCUUACACACGCACACACACUGCAAUCACAUGGCAUUAAAAAAUAUAUUGUGUAUGGAACUUGGCGAGGUCAGUCAGGACCUGGAGCUGUAAUCAUAGCCUUAUUGCCACUUCUUGCGUUGUGUAUACAUUGAAUGGCUCAUAGAUUUUAAGAGAUUUUUUUAUUGUAAGUAUUUCUACUAAAUGCACUUAUCCUUCUAUAUGUUUAUAUAUUUUGGUAAAAUUGAUUUAUCAGAUACUUGGUAUUUUAGUAAGAAAAUUUCCUCAAAUAUUUGGCUAAUGCUUUGAUGUCAAGAUUGCAUAUUGCUGAGUUGGAGCUCAGAAGAAAUGUAUGCAGCUAAAAAUUGCACUGUGUGUUCUUGUGAAUUUGCUCACAAUUCUAAAAUGACAUAAUUGGUGGCUGUGAUGCUUACAGUCACUGCCUACUGGCUCUCUUAUGAUGAAUGUUGCCAUCAUAUGAUCAUUUAUUUACUUUUUGUGCAAGCAAUGGCAUUUUGGUUGUUGCCAAAAACAACACAAGUGGUUGGGAGUGUAUGUUGUUGGAAGGUGUACACUUCUGUUUCUUUCAGCUGUAUUAUUUAUACACCCAGGUUUUCUGUUAAGGAUGUAAUCAUUCAUUCAAGAAAGAACAAUUGGCAAGAAAUAAUUAAAUUACCUUAAAAAGAAUUAAGAGGCACUCCAGCCAGAUAACACCUCCCAACAACAUGAAAUUUAGUUAGUGCUUAGUGAAAUUCCUUAAAUAUAUAUGUAUAUGUUUUCUUCAACAUUAUUUAAUAUAACUACUGCUUUUAUAUUUUUUAAUGGUGUUGCAACCACUUGUACACCUGCUACACCUUACUGACAAAACUGGGCAGCUGAAAAUAAAAGAGAAUAAAUUCUAUUCCACUGUAAGAAGUUGAUUUCUUUUCAGCUUUCUUUGUAUAUCAGUAAAGAACACGAAUUGUUUGAAAAUAAUUUUAAGUCUGAUAAGUAUGGAUAGCAUGUUACCUAAGCUUUUAAUUUGUACAUUUUGAUGUCUGAUCAUUUGCAUGGAAGAGACAAUAGUGCCACGUCUGAAUUGUUCUCUUGUGCUUGGUUAAUAUGUACUUCUCUAGAUUGUUCAAAAAGUUUCAAAUGACAUUCCUUACUCUUUGGUUUUCAGAGGCAUUCAAGCAAAAUAUCACAGUGGUCUUUUGUUUUCUGACCAAUCUAACAAUACCUGUGAUUAAAUUUAAUUUGUUAGUGUAAAUAAAUUUCUUGCCAAUGAGUAUUAUUGUUGUUAGACAACGAAUGCAAUAAAAAGAAAUACUGAGGUCUGUUGAAGCAA